GCAGCUCCAUUAACCGGCAAAAAGCAGCAGAACCUGGAAGUCCACGGGGAGCUUGGAUGCCAAAGGGAGGACGGCUGGGUCCUCUGGAGAGGACUACUCACUGGCAUAUUUCUGAGGUAUCUGUAGAAUAACCACAGCCUCAGAUACUGGGGACUUUACAGUCCCACAGAACCGUCCUCCCAGGAAGCUGAAUCCAGCAAGAACAAUGGAGGCCAGCGGGAAGCUCAUUUGCAGACAAAGGCAAGUCCUUUUUUCCUUUCUCCUUUUGGGCUUAUCUCUGGCGGGCGCGGCGGAACCUAGAAGCUAUUCUGUGGUGGAGGAAACUGAGGGCAGCUCCUUUGUCACCAAUUUAGCAAAGGACCUGGGUCUGGAGCAGAGGGAAUUCUCCAGGCGGGGGGUUAGGGUUGUUUCCAGAGGGAACAAACUACAUUUGCAGCUCAAUCAGGAGACCGCGGAUUUGUUGCUAAAUGAGAAAUUGGACCGUGAGGAUCUGUGCGGUCACACAGAGCCCUGUGUGCUACGUUUCCAAGUGUUGCUAGAGAGUCCCUUCGAGUUUUUUCAAGCUGAGCUGCAAGUAAUAGACAUAAACGACCACUCUCCAGUAUUUCUGGACAAACAAAUGUUGGUGAAAGUAUCAGAGAGCAGUCCUCCUGGGACUACGUUUCCUCUGAAGAAUGCCGAAGACUUAGAUGUAGGCCAAAACAAUAUUGAGAACUAUAUAAUCAGCCCCAACUCCUAUUUUCGGGUCCUCACCCGCAAACGCAGUGAUGGCAGGAAAUACCCAGAGCUGGUGCUGGACAAAGCGCUGGACCGAGAGGAAGAAGCUGAGCUCAGGUUAACACUCACAGCACUGGAUGGUGGCUCUCCGCCCAGAUCUGGCACUGCUCAGGUCUACAUCGAAGUCCUGGAUGUCAACGAUAAUGCCCCUGAAUUUGAGCAGCCUUUCUAUAGAGUGCAGAUCUCUGAGGACAGUCCGGUAGGCUUCCUGGUUGUGAAGGUCUCUGCCACGGAUGUAGACACAGGAGUCAACGGAGAGAUUUCCUAUUCACUUUUCCAAGCUUCAGAAGAGAUUGGCAAAACCUUUAAGAUCAAUCCCUUGACAGGAGAAAUUGAACUAAAAAAACAACUCGAUUUCGAAAAACUUCAGUCCUAUGAAGUCAAUAUUGAGGCAAGAGAUGCUGGAACCUUUUCUGGAAAAUGCACCGUUCUGAUUCAAGUGAUAGAUGUGAACGACCAUGCCCCAGAAGUUACCAUGUCUGCAUUUACCAGCCCAAUACCUGAGAACGCGCCUGAAACUGUGGUUGCACUUUUCAGUGUUUCAGAUCUUGAUUCAGGAGAAAAUGGGAAAAUUAGUUGCUCCAUUCAGGAGGAUCUACCCUUCCUCCUGAAAUCCGCGGAAAACUUUUACACCCUACUAACGGAGAGACCACUAGACAGAGAAAGCAGAGCGGAAUACAACAUCACUAUCACUGUCACUGACUUGGGGACCCCUAUGCUGAUAACACAGCUCAAUAUGACCGUGCUGAUCGCCGAUGUCAAUGACAACGCUCCCGCCUUCACCCAAACCUCCUACACCCUGUUCGUCCGCGAGAACAACAGCCCCGCCCUGCACAUCCGCAGCGUCAGCGCUACAGACAGAGACUCAGGCACCAACGCCCAGGUCACCUACUCGCUGCUGCCGCCCCAGGACCCGCACCUGCCCCUCACAUCCCUGGUCUCCAUCAACGCGGACAACGGCCACCUGUUCGCCCUCAGGUCUCUGGACUACGAGGCCCUGCAGGGGUUCCAGUUCCGCGUGGGCGCUUCAGACCACGGCUCCCCGGCGCUGAGCAGCGAGGCGCUGGUGCGCGUGGUGGUGCUGGACGCCAACGACAACUCGCCCUUCGUGCUGUACCCGCUGCAGAACGGCUCCGCGCCCUGCACCGAGCUGGUGCCCCGGGCGGCCGAGCCGGGCUACCUGGUGACCAAGGUGGUGGCGGUGGACGGCGACUCGGGCCAGAACGCCUGGCUGUCGUACCAGCUGCUCAAGGCCACGGAGCUCGGUCUGUUCGGCGUGUGGGCGCACAAUGGCGAGGUGCGCACCGCCAGGCUGCUGAGCGAGCGCGACGCGGCCAAGCACAGGCUGGUGGUGCUGGUCAAGGACAAUGGCGAGCCUCCGCGCUCGGCCACCGCCACGCUGCACGUGCUCCUGGUGGACGGCUUCUCCCAGCCCUACCUGCCUCUCCCGGAGGCGGCCCCGACCCAGGCCCAGGCCGACUUGCUCACCGUCUACCUGGUGGUGGCGUUGGCCUCGGUGUCUUCGCUCUUCCUCUUUUCGGUGCUCCUGUUCGUGGCGGUGCGGCUGUGUAGGAGGAGCAGGGCGGCCUCGGUGGGUCGCUGCUUGGUGCCCGAGGGCCCCCUUCCAGGGCAUCUUGUGGACAUGAGCGGCACCAGGACCCUAUCCCAGAGCUACCAGUAUGAGGUGUGUCUGGCAGGAGGCUCAGGGACCAAUGAGUUCAAGUUCCUGAAGCCGAUUAUCCCCAACUUCCCUCCCCAGUGCCCUGGGAAAGAAAUACAAGGAAAUUCUACCUUCCCCAAUAACUUUGGGUUCAAUAUUCAGUGACCAUAGUUGACUUUUACAUUCCAUAGGUAUUUUAUUUUGUGGCAUUUCCAUGCCAAUGUUUAUUUCCCCCAAUUUGUGUGUAUGUAAUAUUGUACGGAUUUACUCUUGAUUUUUCUCAUGUUCUUUCUCCCUUUGUUUUAAAGUGAACAUUUACCUUUAUUCCUGGUUCUUAAAAGGUGACAAUUCAUUCUUUAACCCAGAUGGUCUUAAUUUGUAAUUAAUUUGCCUCCCUAAAGAGCAAUACCAAAUCACAUUUUUUUCAUGCCCCUAUCUUUAGCUGAACUUCACCCACUAUUAUGCUUAUGGUAAAAUUAAAUAGAGCAAUUUGGAAGUGAUUCCAAUUUUCCAGCAUUUCUUCAUUUGAUUCUCUUUUUUUAGUCUUAAAAUAAUGACUCCUAUUCAGACAUAUCAUUUUUCUUUUUUGUAAAUCCAGUGCGUUUUUAGUUAACCUUUAAAUAUGCUUUUUGCUUUCAAAAAUAAACCAGAAAACCUAUAUCCUAUGAUACAACUCUAAGUGUUAUCACUUGAUUCGAAAGGGUCAGAAGACCAGUUUUUUAGUAUCCUUUCCUCAUUCAUCCUGGAGAGGAUUGUGCAGGCACAUUAAUAUUGUGACCAAUCACAGAAUCUGGGAAUAUGAAGCUAUAAUUUUUUAAUUAAUGUCACAAAGCUCUAGUGCAAUCUAGUUGAAUGCAGAUGCCUGUGCCCAAAUAAUAAUUCAUAUAGCAUAAAUUGGAGUUGUGUGUUAAUGUGUAAAAAUUUUUGCCUGUACUAUCAUAUAAUUUAAUGUAUAUACACCAGAAACUAUUUUUCAAACUUUUUUUACUGCAACCAAUAGUUAAGAUUAUAUUUUACAUAUUUUGAAACACACAAGCUUAAUAGAAAUAAAUGCUUGUGAACAAUGCUUAGUCUUUUUAUGACAUAAUUUGAAAUUACCUAUAUAUUUCAUUCUAUUCAAUUUUCAAAUGUGGUCAUGAUCCACUAAAUUUAUUUCAUGGUAUACUAGUGGGUAGUAACCCAAAGUUUGAAAACCACUUUUCUCAGACAUAUAAAAGCAUACCAGAUGUUGAACAUUGAUAGUAUCAAAAGAUAGUCCCUUAGGGUUCUAAUUUUAAAAAAAUUUUCAAAGCAUUGUAGGGGAGUAGCUUUGUCUCAUGUUAAAUCACUCUUACCUUUAAGGAUCUGACACACUAUGUAAGAAAAAGACUUCAAGGUUGGAGGAGGAGAUUUUCCAUGACUUUUAUCAAAGUCUACAGUCUAUGUUGUGGGAGAAAAAUGUAGAAUAACAAAAUGAGUAAAAGUAUAGAGGCAAAACAAGCAUGUGUAUGAGAGAGAGAGAGAAAGCAUGGAAAAGAGGAAAUUCAUGGGGAUGAGCAAAAUGACUACUUCCAGUGCCACAGACUAGACUCAGUUGCUUCUCUUAUGUUAUUUUUUGAGACAAGGUCCUGUUCUGUCACCCAGGCUGGAGUGCAGUGGUGUGAUCUCCACUCACUGUGAUCUCCACUCACUGCAACCUCCACCUCCUGGGCUCAAGUGAUCCUCCCACCUCAGCCUCCCUAGUACCCAGGACUACAGGCCCAGGCCACCACACCCACUAAUUUUUGCAUAUUUAGUAGAGACGAGGUUUCAUCAUAUUGCCCAGACUGGUCUCGAAUUCCUGAGCUCAAGCAGUCUGCCUGCCUCAGCCUCCCAAAGUGCUAUGAUUACAGGUAUGAGCACCUGGCCUCAACUACUUCUUGAAGAUAUUUUAAAACUUUAUCUUAACAUUGUAGAGGGACUGGGUAUUAGUCAGUUGAUAAUGCCAAGAAGUGCAAUCUCUUUUAAUAGCAUAUCUAAGACAACCUAAUGUUUAUACUUCUGACUCAGAUUUCACUACUGGUUCUGUUGAGCUUUGUCAACUGAGUAAUUAUUCUUUUCUUUUUUCUUUCUUUGUUUAUGUUUUAGAGACAGGGUCUUAGUCACCUAGGCUGGAGUGCAGUGGUGCAAUCAUAGCUCACUGAAGCCUUGACCUCCUGGGCUCAAGCAAUCCUCCUGACGCAGCAUCCCAAGUAGCCGGGACCACAGGCACAUGCCACCCCCCACAGCUAUUUUUGUUUGUUUGUUUGUUUUUUGUUUUGUUUUGUUUUUGAGGCAGAGUCUCACUCUGUCACCCAGGCUGGAGUGCAGUGGCGCGAUCUCGGCUCACUGCAAGCUCCGCCUCCUGGGUUCCCGCCAUUCUCCUGCCUCAGUCUCCCGAGUAGCACCCCCAGCUAUUUUAAAAAAAAUUUUUGUAGAGAUGGGUUCUCAUCAUGUCGCCCAGGCUGUUGAACUUCUGGCCUCCAAAGGUGGGAGUUAUUCUAGCAGCUUCCCUGUGAUCUUCUCAUAUCUACUGGUGGAGUGGGAAAGAGUAGUUCAAACAACUCAGACAGAAAAUCUCGCUGGUGCAACAGUGGAGAGAAGGGCCAAGUACUUGUCCUGUUACU